ACUUGGCGAGCGGCGCGGGAUGCAGACGGCUGCGAGGCGCUGGGCACAGGAAGAAAAGCAGGAGGAAGGAAUCAGAUGCACAGUUUGUCCUCUGGGGACCUCUGCCUUGAUCCUCAAUAAAUCUCCUUUUAGAUGUCACCUGCAGCAAUUCCCACAGUUCACAAUGAUCUCCAUGGCUUCCGUUGGCCUUAUGGUGAGCUCUGCCAAGAUCUGUAUUCUUGGGCAAGACAGAAUCCUUCUGAAUCUCAGUCUCUUCCUCUAUAAAUGGAAAUAAUUUUGCUCUGCACAAAUCACAAUUAGCAUGUUUGUGGGAAGUCAAACUGUGAAACUCAGCAUAACUGAAAAGCAAUGUACCACUGUUGCUUAUGUGAAAACUCUUGUAAAGCUGUCAGGCACCAUGCACCAUCUAAGUACAGCAGUGUUAGGUAUGAGCCCAUCAGUGAUUAGAGGGGAUGUGGGGUGGAGAGCGGGUCUCUGAGCAGUGGAUCUCCUGGCUUUGGGGAAGCUGGCUCGUUGGCCAUGCCAGGAGCUGAACCUGAAGGUACUCUGUGUGUCCUCUCAACUCCACGGGCCCCACAUUCGCAUUUUUUCCAAUUCCCUCUGGUUUCCAUUUGCUUCCUCCCUCUAGCCCCCUGGCCAUGUCCGAUCUCAACACGAAGUUUCUGAGCUUUUCUCAUUUUGUUCACCAUCUCCAGAACAUCUCUGCUUCUUUUACUUUUCAAAGAAUUUAAACUUGAACUCUGCUCACUCCUGCCCAUCACCAACCUGAGCUCAGAGUUGCUGAGAAGGGAAAGCACCCUCAUAAGGAAGCUCCUCCUUUCCUUACAUCAUUAGACUUGAUCACAGACAGCAUCUCCAUCUCCACACUACUCUGGCCAGGUUGUGCCUCAGUCAAUUACACAACUGUGUCUUAGUAGCCUUGGUAGGGCCCAAAUCAGGAUAUUCUCUGGGAAGAUUCACUUGAUACUAAGCCCAGCAUAAUCUCACUGCAUCUAAAAUAGAAAAUUCUAGACCCACCCCUCCACAUCUUCUUAUUGAUCCCAAUAUGUGACCCAUUUACCAUGUGCUAAAAUCUCUACCUACUGCUGAUUCUCAGAUCAGAUGGUAACCCAGAUUUACCAUGGUCCAAACUCUGACAUCUGAUCAGGGGCAUGUCAUUCUGGUUCAGGCUGUCAGCCCUGAGCAGGUGAGUCAGUUUGCAUCACCCUAAGUGCAGGUUGCCAGGACAACCGUGAGGCUGCAUAAAAAGAACCUAUGACAGGAUGCACAUGAGAGAGACAAGUGGCUUCACAUUGAAGAAGGGGAGGAGUGCGCCAUUGGUUUUCCAUCCUCCAGAUGCACUGAGUAAGCUCCUACCUAACCUGUGUCCCCUCCUUCUUUGAAACACUUCCCAUCCUUUUAAGCCUUGGUAGGAAGGAGAGCCAUCUGGAAGCCCAGAAUCCUAUGGAAUGCUAAGUCUCCCUUCUCCUUACCCCUUAGUGUUGGAAUUCUGGAUACCCAAAGUCUUGGAUUUGACCUUUGUGCACAGUGACUGCAAAGAAGCAUAUUCAUAUUCACAAAAAUGAGCCUUAGAUAAGACUUUCCUCCUCUCGUGGGGGCUCCAGGAAACUGAAAAGCCAAGCUUGUUACCAAUGCUUGCCCUUCCUUAAGUACAUUAUUAAAUACAUCCCCAAUAGUUAAAAGGACUCCUAGACACCCAGGCCAUUCUCCCUCCUUCUAACCCUCAUCUCCUCGGCCUACGAAAGCCCAGCUGUGUGAUCCGGGGAUUGGUUUCCCCUGUCUUCCCCAUCCCAGCAUCCUUCCAGGAAAUAGCCAGUCUCCCUCUCUGCUCUCAGAAGGCAAGUUUCCUUAUCACCUGUGAAUCACAAACCCACAGAGUGGCCAAACGUAGCCGAGCUGAUGCAAGACCCUGGCAAGGGGAAAGCUGCAGGUGUGUUUGUGCUGGGAAGAACUGUGACCCUCACCUCACAGACACCUCCUCUCCUGAUUCUUGGAAGGGUAUAAGGACAGGCCUUCCACCACCAGUCAGGCACACUCUACCACCAUGAAUCCAUUCCUGAUCCUUGCCUUUGUGGGAGCUGCUGUUGCUGUCCCCUUUGACGAUGAUGACAAGAUUGUUGGGGGCUACACCUGUGAGGAGAAUUCUCUCCCCUACCAGGUGUCCCUGAAUUCUGGCUCCCACUUCUGCGGUGGCUCCCUCAUCAGCGAACAGUGGGUGGUAUCAGCAGCUCACUGCUACAAGACCCGCAUCCAGGUGAGACUGGGAGAGCACAACAUCAAAGUCCUGGAGGGGAAUGAGCAGUUCAUCAAUGCGGCCAAGAUCAUCCGCCACCCUAAAUACAACAGGGACACUCUGGACAAUGACAUCAUGCUGAUCAAACUCUCCUCACCUGCCGUCAUCAAUGCCCGCGUGUCCACCAUCUCUCUGCCCACCACCCCUCCAGCUGCUGGCACUGAGUGCCUCAUCUCCGGCUGGGGCAACACUCUGAGCUUUGGUGCUGACUACCCAGACGAGCUGAAGUGCCUGGAUGCUCCGGUGCUGACCCAGGCUGAGUGUAAAGCCUCCUACCCUGGAAAGAUUACCAACAGCAUGUUCUGUGUGGGCUUCCUUGAGGGAGGCAAGGAUUCCUGCCAGCGUGACUCUGGUGGCCCUGUGGUCUGCAACGGACAGCUCCAAGGAGUUGUCUCCUGGGGCCAUGGCUGUGCCUGGAAGAACAGGCCUGGAGUCUACACCAAGGUCUACAACUAUGUGGACUGGAUUAAGGACACCAUCGCUGCCAACAGCUAAAGCCCCCGGUCCCUCUGCAGUCUCUAUACCAAUAAAGUGGCCCUGCUCUCA